AUGUGGCAGUUGGAGCCCCUCGAGGGAAGGGAGCCAUUUUCUUUCCUGGUUUGGGAAAGAGUUGCUCAUCAGUUUGCGGGAGAAGCUGUUUGCCUUCAGCUGAUACACAGUGUAAGGAAAGGCCAAGAUGACAAUGGCCCCGGACGUCAGACUAGAGUAUCUGGAGGAAGUUGCCUCCAUCGUCCUGAAGUUCAAGCCGGACAAGUGGAGCAAGCUGAUAGGCGCCGAGGAGAACGUGGCCCUGUUCACAGAGUUCUUUGAAAAGCCCGACGUCCAGGUGCUGGUGCUGACGCUCAAUGCAGCCGGCAUGAUCAUACCCUGCCUGGGCUUCCCCCAGUCCCUCAAGUCCAAAGGGGUUUACUUCAUCAAGACAAAGUCCGAGAACAUCAACAAGGACAACUACAGGGCCCGGCUCCUUUACGGCGACAUCAGCCCCACACCCGUGGACCAGCUGAUCGCGGUGGUGGAGGAGGUCCUCUCUUCUCUGUUAAACCAAAGUGAGAACAUGGCUGGAUGGCCCCAGGUGGUCUCGGAAGACAUCGUGAAGCAGGUCCACAGGCUGAAGAAUGAAAUGUUUGUGAUGAGUGGCAAGAUCAAAGGCAAAACCUUGCUGCCUAUUCCGGAGCACCUGGGCAGCCUGGAUGGCACGCUGGAGUCCAUGGAGAGGAUCCCCUCUUCACUGGACAACUUGCUCCUGCACGCCAUUGAAACCACCAUCAUCGACUGGUCCCACCAGAUCCGGGAUGUGCUGAGCAAAGACUCAGCCCAGGCGCUGCUGGAUGGGCUGCACCCCCUGCCCCAAGUGGAGUUCGAGUUCUGGGACACUCGGCUGCUGAACCUCAAGUGCAUCCAUGAACAGCUAAACAGACCCAAAGUGAACAAGAUUGUUGAGAUCCUAGAGAAAGCCAAAAGCUGCUACUGGCCAGCCCUGCAAAACGUUUACACCAACGUCACUGAAGGGCUGAAGGAAGCCAACGACAUCGUGCUCUAUUUGAAGCCCCUACGGAUCCUGCUGGAGGAGAUGGAACAAGCCGACUUCACGAUGCUCCCCACCUUCAUUGCCAAGGUGCUGGACACCAUCUGCUUCAUCUGGGCCACCUCUGAGUACUAUAACACACCUGCCAGGAUCAUCGUCAUCCUGCAGGAGUUCUGCAACCAAAUCAUCGAGAUGACACGAACCUUCCUGAGCCCGGAAGAGGUGCUGAAGGGCCUGCAAGGUGAAAUCGAGGAAGUCCUGAGUGGCAUCUCCCUGGCUGUAAAUGUGCUGAAGGAGCUCUACCAGACGUACGACUUCUGCUGCGUGAACAUGAAGCUUUUCUUUAAGGACAAAGAGCCCGUGCCUUGGGAAUUCCCUUCUUCUCUUGCCUUUUCCAGGAUAAAUUCCUUCUUCCAGCGCAUCCAGACCAUUGAGGAACUCUAUAAAACAGCAAUUGAGUUUCUGAAGCUGGAGAAAAUCGAGCUUGGGGGCGUGCGUGGGAACCUCCUCGGGAGCCUGGUGACCCGUAUCUAUGAUGAGGUCUUUGAGCUGGUGAAGGUUUUUGCCGACUGCAAAUAUGAUCCCUUGGACCCUGGAGACUCGAAUUUUGACCGUGAUUAUGCUGAUUUUGAGAUCAAAAUCCAAGACCUGGAUAGGAGGCUGGCCACGAUCUUUUGCCAAGGAUUUGAUGACUGCAGCUGUAUCAAGUCCUCCGCAAAGCUCCUGUACAUGUGUGGGGGCCUCAUGGAGCGGCCCCUGAUUCUUGCCGAGGUGGCGCCCAGGUAUUCAGUCAUGCUGGAGCUGUUUGACGCUGAGCUAGACAAUGCUAAGAUCUUGUACGAUGCCCAGAUGGCGGCCUCCGAGGAGGGGAACAUCCCCCUGAUCCACAAAAACAUGCCUCCCGUGGCCGGGCAGCUCAAAUGGAGCCUGGAGCUGCAGGAGAGGCUAGAGGUGUCCAUGAAACACCUGAAGCACGUCGAACACCCGGUCAUGUCUGGAGCAGAGGCCAAGCUGACCUAUCAGAAGUAUGACGAGAUGAUGGAGCUGCUGAGGUGCCACCGCGAGAAGAUCUACCAGCAGUGGGUGGCGGGCGUGGACCAGGACUGCCACUUUAACCUGGGGCAGCCGCUGAUUCUGCGGGACGCCGCUAGCAACCUCAUCCACGUCAACUUCAGCAAAGCGUUGGUGGCAGUUCUGAGAGAAGUCAAGUAUUUGAAUUUCCAGCAACAGAAAGAGAUUCCAGACAGUGCGGAGAGUCUGUUCUCAGAGAACGAAACUUUCCGGAAGUUUGUGGGCAACCUGGAGCUCAUCGUUGGCUGGUAUAAUGAGAUAAAGACUAUAGUGAAGGCAGUAGAAUUUCUACUAAUAAAGUCAGAACUGGAAGCAAUUGAUGUCAAGUUAUUGAGCGCUGAAACGACAUUAUUCUGGAAUGGCGAAGGUGUGUUUCAGUACAUUCAAGAGGUGCGAGAAAUUCUGCACAACUUGCAGAACAGGAUGCAAAAGGCAAAACAAAAUAUAGAAGGAAUUUCCCAGGCUAUGAAGGACUGGUCGGCCAACCCGCUGUUUGAAAGAAAGGACAAUAAGAAAGAGGCCCUGUUAGACUUGGAUGGAAGAAUUGCCAACCUCAACAAGCGCUACGCAGCAGUCAGGGAUGCUGGAGUGAAGAUCCAAGCCAUGGUUGCAGAAAACGCAGAACUAUUCAGGGCAGACACACUGAGCCUGCCCUGGAAGGAUUAUGUCAUCUACAUUGACGACAUGGUCUUAGAUGAAUUUGACCAGUUCAUUCGCAAAUCUCUGAGUUUCCUAAUGGACAACAUGGUUAUAGAUGAGAGUAUCGCUCCCCUGUUUGAGAUCCGCAUGGAGCUGGACGAGGAUGGGCUGACCUUCAACCCGACCCUGGAGGUGGGCUCAGAUCGCGGCUUCCUGGCACUGAUCGAGGGCCUGGUCAACGACAUCUACAACGUAGCCAGGCUCAUCCCUCGGCUGGCCAAGGACAGGAUGAACUACAAGAUGGACCUGGAAGAUAACACAGACCUCAUAGAGAUGAGGGAGGAGGUGUCCAGCCUGGUCAUCAAUGCCAUGAAGGAGGCCGAGGAGUACCAGGAUUCCUUUGAGAGGUACUCCUACCUCUGGACGGACAACCUGCAGGAGUUUAUGAAGAAUUUCCUGAUAUAUGGGUGUGCAGUCACUGCGGAGGACUUGGACACCUGGACAGAUGACACCAUCCCCAAGACACCGCCCACCCUGGCUCAGUUCCAGGAGCAGAUCGACUCCUACGAGAAGCUGUAUGAGGAGGUGUCCAAGUGCGAGAACACCAAGGUGUUCCACGGCUGGCUGCAGUGCGACUGCCGCCCCUUCAAGCAGGCCCUGCUCAGCACAAUCCGGCGCUGGGGCUUCAUGUUCAAGCGGCACCUGAGCAACCACGUCACCAACAGCCUGGCUGACCUGGAAGCCUUCAUGAAAGUCGCCAGAAUGGGCUUGACCAAGCCCCUCAAGGAGGGGGACUAUGAUGGGCUUGUGGAGGUGAUGGGGCACCUGAUGAAAGUCAAGGAGAGGCAAGCAGCCACCGACAACAUGUUUGAGCCCCUGAAGCAAACCAUCGAGCUGCUCAAGACCUACGGGGAGGAGAUGCCAGAGGAGAUCCACUUGAAGCUGCAGGAGCUGCCGGAGCACUGGGCAAAUACCAAGAAACUGGCCAUUCAGGUGAAGCUGACCGUGGCACCACUCCAGGCCAACGAGGUCAGCAUCCUGCGGCGGAAAUGCCAGCAAUUCGAGCUCAAGCAACAUGAGUUCAGGGAGAGGUUCAGGCGCGAGGCCCCGUUCUCCUUCAGCGACCCCAACCCCUACAAGUCCCUGAAUAAGCAACAAAAGAGCAUCUCCGCCAUGGAAGGCAUCAUGGAGGCGCUGUCCAAGUCCGGGGGCCUGUUCGAGGUCCCCGUCCCAGACUACAAGCAGCUCAAGGCCUGCCACCGGGAGGUCCGCCUACUGAAGGAGCUCUGGGACAUGGUUGUUGUGGUAAAUACCAGCAUCGAGGACUGGAAGACCACCAAGUGGAAAGAUAUCAACGUUGAGCAGAUGGACAUAGAUUGUAAGAAGUUUGCCAAGGACAUGAGGUCUUUGGACAAGGAGAUGAAAACCUGGGAUGCCUUCGUGGGGCUCGACAACACCGUGAAAAACGUGAUCACGUCCCUGCGUGCCGUGAGCGAGCUGCAGAACCCUGCCAUUCGGGAACGCCACUGGCAGCAGCUCAUGCAGGCCACCCAGGUGAAAUUUAAAAUGUCAGAAGAGACGACCCUGGCAGAUUUACUGCAGCUGAACCUCCACAGUUACGAGGAUGAGGUCCGCAACAUCGUGGACAAGGCCGUGAAGGAGUCGGGCAUGGAAAAGGUGCUGAAAGCCCUGGACAGUACCUGGAGCAUGAUGGAAUUCCAGCACGAGCCGCACCCGCGGACAGGCACCAUGAUGCUCAAGUCCAGCGAGGUGCUGGUGGAGACGCUGGAGGACAACCAGGUGCAGCUGCAGAACCUGAUGAUGUCCAAGUACCUGGCCCACUUCCUGAAGGAGGUGACAAGCUGGCAGCAGAAGCUGUCCACGGCGGACUCCGUCAUCUCCAUCUGGUUUGAGGUCCAGCGAACCUGGAGCCACCUGGAGAGCAUCUUCAUCGGCUCCGAAGACAUCCGCACCCAGCUCCCGGGGGACUCCCAGCGCUUUGACGACAUCAACCAGGAAUUCAAGGCCUUGAUGGAAGAUGCAGUGAAAACACCCAACGUGGUGGAAGCCACCAGCAAACCCGGCCUCUACAAUAAACUGGAGGCCCUGAAGAAGAGCUUGGCCAUCUGUGAAAAGGCUUUGGCAGAGUAUUUAGAGACGAAAAGACUGGCUUUCCCCCGGUUCUAUUUUGUCUCCUCGGCUGACCUCCUGGACAUUCUCUCCAAUGGCAAUGACCCCGUGGAGGUGAGCCGCCACCUGUCCAAACUCUUCGAUAGCCUGUGUAAACUGAAGUUCCGGCUCGAUGCCAGUGACAAACCUCUCAAGGUGGGCCUGGGAAUGUACAGCAAGGAGGACGAGUACAUGGUUUUUGAUCAGGAAUGCGACCUCUCGGGGCAGGUGGAAGUGUGGCUGAAUCGAGUGCUGGACCGAAUGUGCUCUACCCUCCGGCACGAAAUCCCAGAGGCCGUGGUGACCUACGAAGAGAAGCCGAGGGAGCAGUGGAUCCUGGACUACCCAGCCCAGGUGGCCCUGACUUGCACCCAGAUCUGGUGGACGACCGAGGUGGGCCUGGCAUUUGCCAGGCUGGAGGAAGGCUAUGAAAACGCUAUCAGAGAUUAUAACAAAAAGCAGAUUAGCCAGCUGAACGUACUCAUCACGCUGCUCAUGGGGAACCUCAACGCUGGCGACAGGAUGAAGAUCAUGACCAUCUGCACCAUCGAUGUGCACGCACGGGACGUGGUGGCCAAAAUGAUCGUGGCCAAGGUGGAGAGUUCUCAGGCCUUCACCUGGCAGGCCCAGCUCCGGCAUCGCUGGGACGAAGAGAAGCGACACUGCUUUGCCAACAUCUGCGAUGCCCAAAUCCAGUAUUCCUAUGAGUAUCUGGGCAACACGCCGCGGCUGGUCAUCACCCCACUCACUGACAGGUGCUAUAUCACCCUGACCCAGUCCCUCCAUCUCAUCAUGGGUGGAGCCCCUGCCGGCCCCGCUGGGACCGGCAAGACUGAGACGACCAAGGACCUGGGCAGAGCCCUGGGCACCAUGGUCUACGUCUUCAACUGCUCCGAGCAGAUGGACUACAAGUCCUGUGGAAAUAUCUACAAGGGCCUGGCCCAGACGGGAGCCUGGGGCUGCUUUGACGAGUUUAAUCGCAUCUCAGUGGAAGUCUUGUCUGUGAUUGCCGUGCAGGUAAAAUGUGUCCAGGAUGCAAUUCGGGCCAAGAAAAAAGCAUUCAAUUUCCUGGGAGAGAUCAUAGGCCUCAUUCCCACCGUCGGUAUCUUCAUCACCAUGAACCCUGGGUACGCCGGACGCGCGGAGCUGCCUGAGAACCUAAAAGCCUUAUUCAGGCCCUGUGCCAUGGUCGUCCCCGACUUCGAACUGAUAUGUGAGAUCAUGCUCAUGGCCGAGGGCUUUCUGGAAGCCCGCCUUCUGGCCAGGAAGUUCAUCACCCUGUACACCUUGUGCAAGGAGCUGCUCUCGAAGCAGGAUCAUUACGACUGGGGCCUGAGAGCCAUCAAGUCUGUGCUGGUGGUGGCCGGCUCCCUGAAGAGGGGCGACCCCAGCCGGGCAGAGGACCAGGUGCUCAUGCGGGCGCUGAGAGACUUCAACAUCCCCAAGAUUGUGACAGACGACCUGCCCGUAUUCAUGGGACUGAUCGGGGACCUCUUCCCGGCUCUGGACGUGCCUCGGAAACGGGACCUGAAUUUUGAAAAGAUCAUCAAGCAGAGCAUCGUGGAGCUCAAGCUGCAGGCGGAGGACAGCUUCGUGCUGAAGGUGGUGCAGCUGGAGGAGCUGCUGCAGGUCCGCCACUCCGUGUUCAUCGUCGGGAAUGCGGGCAGCGGCAAAUCUCAGGUCCUCAAAUCCCUCAACAAGACCUAUCAGAACCUGAAGAGGAAGCCGGUCGCCGUGGACCUGGACCCCAAGGCCGUCACCUGCGACGAGCUCUUUGGCAUCAUCAACCCAGUGACCAGGGAAUGGAAAGAUGGCCUGUUCUCCACCAUCAUGCGAGACCUGGCCAACAUCACCCAUGACGGCCCCAAGUGGAUCAUCCUUGACGGAGACAUAGACCCCAUGUGGAUCGAGUCUCUCAACACAGUCAUGGAUGACAACAAGGUCCUCACCCUGGCCAGCAACGAGCGGAUCCCCCUGAACCGCACCAUGAGGCUGGUGUUCGAAAUCAGCCACCUGAGGACGGCCACCCCAGCCACCGUUUCCAGAGCCGGCAUCCUCUACAUCAACCCAGCCGACCUGGGAUGGAACCCGGUGGUGAGCAGCUGGAUCGAGAGGCGCAAGGUGCAGUCGGAGAAGGCCAACCUGAUGAUCCUCUUUGACAAGUACCUGCCCACGUGCCUGGACAAGUUGCGCUUUGGGUUCAAGAAGAUCACGCCAGUGCCGGAGAUCACGGUGAUCCAAACGAUUCUGUACCUGCUGGAGUGCCUGCUCACGGAGAAGACCGUGCCCCCCGACUCCCCCAGGGAGCUGUACGAGCUGUACUUCGUGUUCACCUGCUUCUGGGCCUUCGGUGGCGCCAUGUUCCAGGACCAGCUUGUGGAUUAUCGAGUGGAGUUCAGUAAAUGGUGGAUCAACGAAUUCAAGACUAUCAAGUUCCCCUCGCAGGGAACGAUUUUUGACUACUACAUUGAUCCUGACACAAAAAAGUUCCUGCCCUGGACAGAUAAAGUGCCCUCCUUUGAGCUGGAUCCCGAUGUCCCACUGCAGGCCUCUUUGGUCCACACCACGGAAACCAUCCGCAUCCGCUACUUCAUGGACCUGCUCAUGGAGAAGUCCUGGCCGGUGAUGCUGGUGGGGAACGCGGGGACGGGCAAGUCGGUGCUGAUGGGGGACAAGCUGGAAAGCCUGAACACGGACAACUACCUGGUGCAGGCUGUGCCCUUCAACUUCUACACGACCUCAGCCAUGCUGCAGGGGGUGCUGGAGAAGCCGCUGGAGAAGAAAUCGGGGAGGAACUACGGGCCGCCAGGCACUAAGAAGCUCGUCUACUUCAUCGACGACAUGAACAUGCCCGAGGUGGACAAGUAUGGGACGGUGGCCCCGCACACCCUCAUCCGGCAGCACAUGGACCACCGGCACUGGUAUGACAGACAUAAGCUGACGUUAAAAGAUAUCCAUAAUUGUCAGUACGUGGCCUGCAUGAACCCCACUUCCGGAUCCUUCACCAUCGACUCCAGGCUUCAGCGCCAUUUCUGCGUGUUUGCUGUGAGCUUCCCCGGCCAGGAGGCCCUCACCACCAUCUACAACACAAUCCUGACGCAGCACCUGGCCUUCCGCUCGGUCUCCAUGGCUAUCCAGAGGAUAAGCAGCCAGCUGGUGGCCGCGGCCCUGGCUUUGCAUCAGAAAAUCACGGCAACAUUUCUUCCCACGGCCAUUAAGUUUCAUUAUGUCUUCAACCUCAGGGACCUCUCCAAUAUUUUCCAGGGACUCUUAUUUUCCACAGCAGAAGUUCUGAAAACCCCACUGGACCUCGUCCGCCUUUGGCUACAUGAGACUGAACGAGUGUAUGGUGACAAAAUGGUUGACGAAAAAGACCAGGAAACAUUGCAUAGAGUCACCAUGGCCUCCACCAAGAAGUUCUUUGAUGAUCUUGGUGAUGAACUCUUAUUUGCCAAGCCAAAUAUCUUCUGCCACUUUGCUCAAGGGAUUGGCGAUCCCAAAUAUGUUCCUGUAACCGACAUGGCUCCUCUGAACAAGCUCCUCGUGGACGUCCUGGACAGCUACAAUGAAGUUAAUGCAGUCAUGAAUUUGGUGCUGUUUGAGGACGCCGUGGCUCACAUCUGCAGGAUUAAUCGCAUCCUGGAGUCUCCCCGGGGGAAUGCCCUGCUGGUGGGGGUGGGCGGCAGUGGCAAACAGAGCCUCUCCCGCCUGGCAGCGUACAUCAGCGGGCUUGACGUGUUUCAGAUCACCCUCAAGAAGGGCUACGGGAUCCCCGACCUCAAGAUUGACCUCGCUGCUCAGUACAUAAAGGCUGCCGUGAAGAACGUUCCCUCGGUGUUCCUGAUGACAGACUCCCAGGUGGCCGAGGAGCAGUUUCUGGUGCUGAUCAAUGACCUGCUGGCCUCAGGAGAGAUCCCUGGGCUGUUUAUGGAGGACGAGGUGGAGAACAUCAUCUCCUCCAUGCGACCCCAAGUCAAGUCCCUUGGCAUGAAUGACACUCGGGAAACAUGUUGGAAGUUCUUCAUCGAAAAAGUGCGCAGACAGCUCAAGGUGAUCCUGUGUUUCUCCCCUGUGGGCUCCGUGCUGCGGGUACGAGCCAGAAAGUUCCCAGCUGUGGUCAACUGCACGGCCAUCGACUGGUUCCACGAGUGGCCGGAAGAUGCGCUGGUGUCCGUCAGCGCCCGCUUCCUGGAGGAGACUGAGGGGAUUCCGUGGGAAGUCAAGGCCUCCAUCAGCUUCUUCAUGUCCUACGUGCACACCACCGUCAACGAGAUGUCCAGGGUAUACCUGGCUACUGAGAGGCGCUACAACUACACCACACCCAAAACCUUUCUGGAGCAGAUCAAACUGUACCAGAACCUGCUGGCCAAGAAGAGAACGGAACUUGUUGCCAAAAUCGAGAGGCUGGAGAACGGCCUGAUGAAGCUGCAGAGCACGGCUUCCCAGGUGGAUGAUUUGAAAGCCAAGUUGGCGAUUCAGGAGGCUGAGCUCAAGCAGAAGAAUGAGAGCGCAGACCAACUGAUCCAGGUGGUCGGCAUCGAGGCCGAGAAGGUCAGCAAAGAGAAGGCCAUUGCUGACCAGGAAGAAGUCAAGGUCGAGGUCAUCAAUAAGAACGUCACUGAGAAGCAAAAGGCCUGUGAAACAGACCUGGCCAAAGCAGAACCGGCCCUGCUGGCAGCCCAGGAGGCUCUGGACACUCUGAAUAAGAACAACCUGACAGAGCUGAAGUCCUUUGGGUCCCCGCCGGAUGCUGUGGUCAACGUCACCGCCGCCGUCAUGAUUCUGACCGCACCUGGGGGCAAGAUCCCCAAGGACAAGAGCUGGAAGGCGGCCAAGAUCAUGAUGGGCAAGGUGGACACCUUCCUAGACUCCCUGAAGAAGUUCGACAAGGAGCACAUCCCUGAGGCCUGCCUGAAGGCCUUCAAGCCCUACCAAGGCAACCCGACGUUCGACCCCGAGUUCAUCCGCUCCAAGUCCACGGCCGCCGCCGGCCUGUGCUCCUGGUGCAUCAACAUCGUCCGCUUCUACGAGGUCUACUGCGACGUGGCGCCCAAGAGGCAGGCACUGGAGGAGGCUAAUGCAGAGCUGGCAGAGGCACAAGAGAAGCUGUCCCGGAUCAAAAACAAGAUUGCCGAACUUAACGCCAACCUGAGCAACCUAACCUCAGCGUUUGAAAAAGCAACAGCUGAGAAAAUCAAGUGUCAGCAAGAGGCCGAUGCCACGAACAGGGUGAUCUUACUGGCGAACAGGCUGGUCGGGGGAUUAGCAUCGGAAAACAUCCGCUGGGCUGAGUCUGUGGAGAACUUCAGGAGCCAGGGGGUCACGCUGUGUGGGGACGUCCUGCUCAUCUCUGCCUUCGUGUCCUACGUGGGCUACUUCACCAAGAAAUACCGGAAUGAGCUGAUGGAGAAAUUCUGGAUCCCUUACAUACAUAACUUAAAGGUCCCCAUCCCGAUCACGAAUGGCCUGGAUCCCUUGAGCCUGCUGACAGAUGACGCGGACGUGGCCACCUGGAACAACCAGGGCCUCCCCAGCGACCGCAUGUCCACCGAGAAUGCCACCAUCCUGGGCAACACCGAGCGGUGGCCGCUGAUCGUGGACGCCCAGCUCCAAGGAAUCAAGUGGAUCAAAAACAAAUACAGGAGUGAACUGAAAGCCAUCCGCCUGGGACAGAAGAGCUACCUGGAUGUCAUCGAGCAGGCCAUCUCGGAAGGGGACACCUUGCUCAUUGAGAACAUCGGCGAAACCGUGGACCCCGUGCUGGACCCUCUACUGGGCAGGAACACGAUUAAAAAGGGAAAGUACAUUAAGAUCGGUGACAAGGAGGUGGAGUACCACCCCAAGUUCCGCCUGAUCCUACACACCAAGUACUUCAACCCACACUACAAGCCAGAGAUGCAGGCUCAGUGCACCCUCAUCAACUUCCUGGUCACCAGGGAUGGACUCGAGGACCAACUCUUGGCCGCUGUGGUGGCCAAAGAGCGCCCAGAUCUGGAACAGCUGAAGGCAAACCUCACCAAGUCUCAAAACGAAUUUAAGAUUGUUCUGAAAGAGCUGGAAGAUUCGCUCCUGGCCCGUCUGUCGGCUGCGUCGGGGAACUUUCUGGGAGACACGGCCUUGGUGGAGAAUCUGGAGACCACCAAGCACACAGCCAGCGAGAUCGAGGAGAAGGUGGUGGAGGCAAAAAUCACAGAAGUUAAAAUCAACGAAGCGAGAGAGAACUACCGCCCGGCUGCGGAGAGGGCAUCUCUGCUCUACUUCAUACUGAACGAUCUCAACAAAAUCAACCCCGUCUACCAGUUCUCCCUCAAGGCCUUCAACGUGGUGUUUGAGAAAGCCAUCCAGAGGACCACCCCUGCCAACGAGGUGAAGCAGCGGGUGAUCAACCUGACGGACGAGAUCACCUACUCCGUCUACAUGUACACGGCCCGGGGACUCUUCGAGAGGGACAAACUCAUUUUCCUGGCACAAGUUACGUUUCAGGUCCUGUCCAUGAAGAAGGAGCUGAACCCAGUGGAGCUGGAUUUCCUCCUGCGGUUCCCUUUUAAGGCCGGAGUGGUCUCACCAGUGGACUUCCUCCAGCAUCAAGGCUGGGGCGGGAUCAAGGCCCUCUCGGAGAUGGAUGAGUUCAAAAAUCUGGACAGUGACAUCGAAGGAUCUGCCAAGCGCUGGAAAAAGCUGGUGGAGUCGGAAGCCCCCGAGAAGGAGAUCUUCCCCAAGGAGUGGAAGAACAAGACGGCCCUGCAGAAGCUGUGCAUGGUGCGCUGCCUGCGGCCAGAUCGCAUGACCUACGCUAUCAAGAACUUCGUGGAGGAAAAGAUGGGCAGCAAGUUCGUGGAAGGCCGGAGUGUUGAGUUUUCUAAGUCCUACGAGGAGAGCAGCCCCUCCACGUCAAUCUUCUUCAUCCUCUCCCCGGGGGUUGACCCCUUGAAAGACGUGGAAGCCCUGGGAAAAAAACUAGGGUUUACCAUAGACAAUGGAAAACUCCAUAAUGUGUCCCUGGGGCAGGGACAAGAGGUGGUGGCUGAGAACGCCCUGGACGUGGCUGCAGAGAAAGGACACUGGGUCAUUCUGCAGUCUUGGCUGCAGAAUAUCCACCUGGUGGCCCGGUGGCUGGGAACACUGGACAAGAAGCUGGAGCACUACAGCACGGGCAGCCAUGAGGACUACCGGGUGUUCAUCAGCGCGGAGCCUGCCCCCAGCCCCGAGACCCACAUCAUCCCCCAGGGCAUUCUGGAGAACGCCAUCAAGAUCACCAACGAGCCCCCCACGGGCAUGCACGCCAACUUGCACAAGGCCCUGGACCUGUUCACCCAGGACACCCUGGAGAUGUGCACCAAGGAGAUGGAGUUCAAGUGCAUGCUCUUCGCCCUGUGCUACUUCCACGCUGUGGUGGCAGAGAGGCGCAAGUUCGGCGCCCAGGGCUGGAACCGGUCGUACCCCUUCAACAACGGGGACCUCACCAUCUCCAUCAACGUGCUCUACAACUACCUGGAGGCCAACCCCAAGGUGCCCUGGGACGAUCUCCGCUACCUUUUUGGUGAAAUCAUGUAUGGCGGCCACAUCACAGAUGACUGGGACCGUCGGCUGUGCAGGACCUACCUGGCUGAAUACAUCCGGACGGAGAUGCUGGAGGGAGACGUCCUGCUGGCCCCCGGCUUUCAGAUCCCCCCCAACCUGGACUACAAGGGUUACCACGAAUACAUCGAUGAGAACCUGCCCCCUGAGAGUCCCUAUCUGUAUGGCCUGCACCCCAACGCAGAGAUUGGCUUUCUGACGGUCACCUCAGAGAAGCUGUUCCGCACUGUCCUGGAAAUGCAGCCAAAAGAGACGGACUCGGGGGCAGGCACGGGAGUGUCCCGCGAGGAGAAGGUGAAGGCCGUGCUGGACGACAUCCUGGAGAAGAUUCCGGAGACUUUCAACAUGGCUGAGAUCAUGGCAAAGGCAGCGGAAAAGACCCCCUACGUGGUAGUCGCCUUUCAAGAAUGUGAAAGAAUGAACAUCCUGACCAACGAAAUGCGCCGUUCGCUCAAGGAGCUGAACCUGGGGCUGAAGGGAGAACUGACCAUCACGACCGACGUGGAAGAUCUGUCCACGGCUCUCUUCUAUGACACCGUGCCUGAUACGUGGGUGGCCCGGGCCUACCCCUCCAUGAUGGGCCUGGCGGCCUGGUACGCAGACCUGCUGCUCCGCAUCAGGGAACUCGAGGCCUGGACGACAGACUUUGCCCUGCCCACCACCGUGUGGCUGGCCGGCUUCUUCAACCCCCAGUCGUUCCUCACGGCCAUCAUGCAGUCCAUGGCCAGGAAGAACGAGUGGCCCCUGGACAAGAUGUGUCUGUCUGUCGAGGUGACCAAGAAAAACCGAGAGGACAUGACCGCUCCUCCGCGAGAGGGCUCCUACGUGUACGGACUCUUCAUGGAAGGGGCUCGCUGGGACACCCAGACUGGAGUCAUCGCUGAAGCGCGGCUGAAAGAGCUGACCCCGGCCAUGCCUGUCAUCUUCAUCAAGGCCAUUCCUGUGGACCGCAUGGAGACCAAGAACAUCUAUGAGUGUCCCGUGUACAAAACACGCAUCCGCGGCCCCACCUAUGUCUGGACCUUUAACUUGAAGACCAAAGAGAAGGCAGCGAAGUGGAUCCUGGCAGCCGUGGCGCUGCUCCUACAGGUUUAGCUCGCUCCUGCCUCACAGCCCACACUCCCUGGGGCUGGACCACAACUCAGCCCUUCACCUGUGCACCUGUGACUUAUUCUUUACAGGAACUGGUGGUGGUUUUUCGUUCUCUUAAAUAAUCAGGUGCUUUGUAACCAAGCACAUCGGAACCAGAGGGUGGAGGUUGGUGUGGAAGAGGUGGGGCAGAUUAAAGCCAGUGGAGCCACUCA